AUUGUAUAUAUUCCUACCAGAUGGAGAUAAUUACAGCUUUAAAAAUUUUUAUUUUUUCAUUUUAUUUCACACAUUGACAUUAAAUUUUUAUGGACACAUAAUAACUGUACAUAUAUAUGGGGUAGAAUGUGAUGUUUUAAUACAUGUACUCAAUGUGUAAUGAUCAAAUCAGGGUAAUUUGCAUAAUGAUUUUUCUGUAGGGAGAAAAUUCAAAAUCUACUCUUCUGGCUAUUUUCAAAUAUAUAAUAUGUUAUUGUUAACUAUACUCAUCCUACUAUGCAAUAGGACACCAGAACUUAUUCCUGGGUUCUACAUCCGUUAAGGCAACCAAGGAUUGGAAAUAUUGGAAAAAAAAAUUGCGUCUGUACUGAACAUGUACAGACUUUUUUCUUGUCCUUAUUCCUUACACAAUAUAGUACAAUAACUAUUUGCAUGACAUUUACAUCGGAUAUUAUGAGUGAUCUAGAGUUGAUAUGAAGUAUAUGGGAGGAUGUGCAAAGGUGAUGUGCAAAUACUAUGUCAUUUUAUAUCAGGGACUUGAGUAUCCUUUGUUACCCUCAGGAGAUCCUGAAACCAGUCCCCCAUGGAUACUGAGGGCUGACUGUAUAGUCCUAUCCUCACGGAACUUUCAUUCUAAUGGGGGAAGACUGACUAUAAACAAAAUAUAUGUAAUAGGUGGUGGUAAGUACCGUGGAGAAGUAACAAACGGGGCAAAGUGAGUUAUACAGCUCCAUUCUUAGAAACCUUGGAGUACUUUUCUUAGUUUAUACUUGUGGUGGUUUCCUUUUGUCUCCUUUAUUACAUGGGACUCUGACAUGUGCCCAUAGCUAGGGUGACAGUAGGAUCUACCCGAUAGUAGGGUGGCAGUAGGAUCUACCCAAAAAGCGUCCUGCUGAUACAGGACCAAAGCAUCCUGUUGUUCUCGAGCCUAUAAAAAGAGCUAAUGGUCUUGCUUCUCUUAACUGUGGCCUCCUACACUGUGUUUUGGAUGAUUGGUGAUGUCUUGGAUAUUCUGUUUCUUUGGAACUUUGAAUAUACAACACUUUACUAGGGAAUUAGCAAUGGAAGCAGAGCAAAGAUGUACAGAGGAAACAAUGCGUAACUCUGAUGGAAUUGAAGUCAUGAGGCAGCAGAGAGCUUAAAUUACAGCUUUAAAAAUUUUUAUUUUUUAGAGGGAAUUUACUUGGGAGUAACAGCAGUAAUAGUUAACGGAGCCAGAAUGCUUGAGUCAUAUAAUUGCAAAGCAGAGUUGGGAGCAACAGAUGCUAAAGAGUAGUUGCUGUAGUUCCUCUUUGGGUCGUAGGAGCAGUUGUCAUAUUCCUAUAUAGCUACUGCAUGAAGAAGAGUUCUUAGUGAGGCCUGGGUGAACAGCUCUUCUUAGUAUUCUGUGUGACCCCAUUUGACCUUUUAACAAAUCCCUAAGUAAAUAAAUAGCCCCUCAGGUAAACUAAGUUUUUCUCUGCUGUUUUUUUGCUUGAGAGAGCUAUAACUGUAAUAGACUUAUAUUUCUGAACAUUUCAGUGCUUGCCAAUAUUUGGUAAUAUUUAUGUUUCCUAUAUUUGUAAUGAACAUUCUUCUUCCGGUACAUUUUUUGUUAAAUUAUUGUUUGAUGGAUAAAAGUUCACCCUUUAUUGUAUAAAAUUGACUGAGAUUAAUUUAUACACAUUGACAAUGGGUAAAUAGAAUUUUUCAGAUUAUUAAAAGCUGAAGGAUGCCCACGUAAGCAAAAAAAAAAAAGAAAAAACCAACAAAAAUAAACCCAAACCCCUCAAACAAUUUCGAACACGAAACAUUCUUCUGAUGCCGGCAUCCCUGCUUGCAGGUGUGAAGGGGGCAGGAAUCAGCGAGGUGUCCUGGGCUGAGUCCCCGGAGUGGGAAGAGGUGGCAGGAAGGGGAUCUGAGGAGGAGAACAGGGGUCCUGGUGGUCUGUGCUUCUUCCCAGACACGGGAGCUGUAGAGGAGACCUCUGCAGCAGAUGCUAGGGGGGCCAGUAGGCCCAGGCAGUCUUGGGACUUGGGUCUGUCCUGCUGUGCAUCCAUAGUGGGUGCUUUAGAAACGGGAGGCCCACCCGAAGUCCCUGUUGCAAGUGAGGACAAAGUGUGGGAAGGCCGUGAGGGUCUGCAGUCCGGGAUGGCCUUGUCCUCAACGUGCAGUGCACUGUUGAUGCGCUGGAAUGCCGUCUCUUUUUCCAGGUGCAGGUCUUCAGCCGUGACCCGGUACCCCAGCUCUAAGGGAGGUGGCAGCAUCAAAGGCUCCCCUCGCCUGCGUGGCAGCAGGGGAAUCUUGCGUCUACGGGGCCUAGAGUCCUGGGAUCUGGGGGAGCCACCCGUUGGGGCGAUUGUCUGCCCUGGUGCUGUAUCUGCCCCCUUUUCACACCGUGUGUGACCCGAAGAGACAGCCUGAGGCCUGUCCUCACUCACUGUCUUUGAGUAACUGAGGGUCAGCUGGCAGCGGGAUGAGGCUGGCCCCCUCCUCUGCUUUAGCCCCGGCAAGCCUCCCGUGGAGCUGUAGGAGCUGGAGAUGGCAUUUCGUUUGGUGCUCGAGCUCGUCCAGGAUGUCUGGGAUGUGUGGUUAUAUCUGAUUUCUGAGCUCUGGGCGUGGAGGUCUGUCUGCAGAGGCCCGGGCCUGGGCACAAAGGGAGAGGGGCCUCCAUUGUCCCGCAGGGGCCAAAAUGCAGACCGUGCAUCCCCGGUGACCUCGGGGACCGUUCUCUGAUCAUCAGGAUUUUCUUGGACUCUGGGGUCCUUGUCCUGCUCAGGCAUCCCUGCCCCGCUCUCCUUGAGGGCCCUCAACACUAUCUUCCCUGGACACAAGUCUGGGGACAGCCGGGUGUUGUGGACCCCAAAGGGGUGACUACCUGCUCCUGGGCCCCACAGAGUCC